ACGCGCACCUCCCCCAACUCAACUGCCGUUCGUCGUUCGUGGAUGUCCGUUGUGUCCCGAGACUAGGACGUGGCUCCAGGUGCGCCCUGCCCCGCGGCGAGGUUCCCAGAAUGGCCCUUCCCAGCCCCUACCGAAAUCCUAGCGAAGCCCCCCCAUAUUGUGGGAGAGAUACCCCUGCGUCAGGGCCCCCCAGAUCCUGACCACUUGGGAGGCCGAGGCGGGCGGAUCACGAGGUCAGAAGAUAGAGACCAUCCCGGGGAAGUGAAACCCCGUCUCUACUAAAAAUACAAAAAAUUAGCCAGGCGUAGUGGCACGCGCCUAUAAUCCCAGCUACUCAGGAGGCUGGGGCAGGAGAACUGCUUGAACCUGGAAGGCAGAGGUUGCAGUGAGCUGAGAUCGCGCCACUGCACUCCAGCCUGGGUGACAAGAGUGAGACUCCGUCUCAAAAAAAAAAAAAAAAAUCCUGACCACAUCCCCUCAGAUAUACUGAAAGGAGUCCACCAGGAAAUCUUAUAGUUGACCCCCGAAAUCCUGUCAGAAUCGUCUAGAAAUUGUCAGACUUCUCCCUCAGAGCCUGCCAGAAACUUUCCCCAAAAUCCUAUUACUCUCCCCAGAUCAGCAGAGCCACCUAGACUCGUGUCAGAGAUCCCCAGAAAUCCUGGCAGGUCCCCUCCCAAACCCAGUCGGACCUCAGAUUCCGUCAGAGAGCACAGAAGUCCAUCAAAGACACCCCAGAAACGGAGACCCCGAAAUGCACUCAGAGACCCCCGCAGAAAUCAAGACCCUCCAAAUCCAGCCAGAGACCCCCAGAAAUCCAGUCAGACCCCUGCAGAAAUCAAGACCCCCAAAAUCCAGCCAGAGACCCCCAGAAAUCCAGAGACCCCCGCAUAAAUCAAGACCCCCAAAAUCCAGAGACCCCGAAUAAAUCAAGACCCCCAAAAUCCAGUCAGAGAACCCCCAGAAAUCCAAUCAGACCCCCGCAGAAAUCAAGACCCCCGAAAUCCAGCCAGAGACCCCUGAAAUCCAGUCAGAGACCCCCACAGAAAUCAAAAUCUCCAAAAUCCAGCCAGACACUCCCCAGAAAUCCAGUCAGAGACCCCCCCAAAAUCCUGUCAGAGCCCUUGAAAGCCCGCCAAGGCCCACACCACCCAGAGCUCCUGCCAGGGCCCCAUCCUGCUUCAGUGUCCCCGUCUCAGUCCCGUCAGACCCCCGAGAUCAACCAACACCCCCGGGGUCCCUCAGGACUCCAUCCCGAACCCACUCCGUGCGCCAGGGCCCAGCCAAGGCCAUCGCCCCCCUUUGCACCCUGCAGGGUGUUCCAGACCCUGGAAGGGCCUCUCUUCAAAGACCCGUGUUUCCAGAACGGUGGCAGCGGGCUCACGUGGCUUGGGGAGAGCAGGCACUGGGGGAGCUGGGUGAGGACAGGCGAGCCCAGGCUCGACUGGUGGCCCCAAGGGGCGCCCGUGCCCGCUGUGAUGAUAGCAGCGCCCAGGUCUCUCUCUAGCCCCCAGAGUGCGGCCACUAAGGUUUUGGGUCGGCCUGGGUGGAAUGGAGGCAGGAUGGGGCCCCCCAAACUCCUGUCACUGCUGCAGGGACUGCCCAGAGCAGCUGCAAGUGGGGCUGGCAGGGAUGAGGAGGAGGUGGCCUGGGCUUGGGGGACCAUGUACAUCCUGAGUUGGAACCCAGGGGAGCAGCAGGUUUGGGGCCAUGAUGAGGAGAGACCUAGGGGUUGCCCGACGGAGAGAAAAGGGACAGGAAGAGGCAGGAGCUUCAGAGACUACUCAAUGCCACUCUAGCCUGAGGGACUGGAACUUAGUCCGGGGGCAUUAGGGAGCCAUGGGAGGAUCAGGAGCAGGGGCAAGUCAGGAUCAAACUCCCAUGAGAAGCCAGCCGGCCAAAUCCAGGCUGAUGUGGCAAGAAUGGCAGCUGCCCAGGGCUGUGUGGGAGCCAGACACGGCCCCUCGCUUCCCGGAAGAGGCCACGUGAAGCCGAAGCAGGAUGCAGGAGGGCGUCCCAGGCAGAGACCUGGGCAUGGGAGCGGUCCGCAGCUCAGAGUGGCUGGAGCAUCAUGUGCGAUUUGGGGUGCUGAGGAGUGCUCGGGCCAGCUGGUCCUUUUCCCAUCCCUCCCCAUGAAGGAGGGAGGCUGGUAGCUUUGCCAGCAGCUGCGCCGCGGCAGGGGUGGCCCAUGGACCUGCCCGAGGGCCCGGUGGGUGGCCCCACUGCGGAAAUGUACCUCCGGGAGCGGCCUGAGGAGGCAAGGCUGGGAAUGCCGGUCAGCUUGGAGGAGCAAAUACUCAACUCCACGUUCGAAGCUUGUGACCCUCAGAGGACAGGCACUGUGGCUGUGGCCCAGGUGCUGGCCUACCUGGAGGCUGUGACAGGCCAGGGCCCCCAGGAUGCACGCCUCCAAACAUUGGCCAACAGCCUGGACCCCAAUGGGGAGGGCCCUAAGGCCACUGUGGACUUGGACACUUUCCUGGUUGUCAUGCGUGACUGGAUUGCUGCCUGUCAACUACAUGGGGGAUUAGAGCUGGAAGAGGAGACCGCCUUCCAGGGAGCCCUGACCUCCCGGCAACUGCCAUCUGGAUGCCCAGAAGCUGAGGAGCCAGCCAACCUGGAGAGCUUCGGAGGCGAAGACCCCAGACCCGAGCUACAAGCCACAGCUGACCUGCUGAGCAGCCUGGAGGACCUGGAGCUCAGCAACCGACGUCUGGUUGGGGAGAAUGCCAAAUUGCAGCGGAGCAUGGAGACAGCUGAGGAGGGGUCAGCACGCCUUGGGGAGGAGAUCUUGGCUCUGCGUAAGCAGCUUCACAGCACCCAGCAGGCCCUGCAGUUUGCCAAGGCCAUGGAUGAGGAGCUGGAGGACCUGAAGACUCUGGCCAGGAGCCUGGAGGAACAGAAUCGCAGCCUUCUGGCCCAAGCCCGGCAGGCGGAAAAGGAGCAGCAGCAUCUGGUGGCUGAGAUGGAGACUCUGCAGGAGGAGAACGGGAAGCUGCUUGCCGAGCGGGAUGGAGUGAAAAAGAGAAGUCAGGAGCUGGCCAUGGAGAAGGACACUUUGAAGCGGCAGCUCUUUGAGUGUGAACACCUCAUUUGCCAAAGAGACACCAUCCUCUCUGAGCGCACUCGCGAUGUGGAGAGCCUGGCCCAGACCCUGGAAGAAUACAGAGUGACGACGCAGGAACUGAGGCUGGAGAUUUCACGCCUGGAGGAGCAGCUGAGUCAGACCUAUGAGGGGCCCGAUGAGCUACCUGAAGGGGCCCAGCUGAGAAGAGUGGGCUGGACCGAGCUGCUACCCCCAUCGCUGGGCUUGGAGAUCGAGGCCAUUCGACAGAAACAGGAAGUGGCAACUGCUGAUCUCUCCAACCCUCUGUGUGGGGUGUGGCAGUGGGAGGAAGUCAUCCAUGAGACCAGUGAGGAAACUGAGUUUCCAUCUGAAGCCCCAGCUGGGGGACAGAGAAACUUCCAGGGAGAGCCAGCGCACCCUGAAGAAGGAAGGAAGGAGCCAUCCAUGUGGUUGACCAGAAGAGAGGAAGAGGAGGAUGCAGAGAGCCAGGUCACGGCUGAUCUCCCUGUCCCUCUAGGAGCCCCUCGCCCUGGAGACAUCCCAGAAAACCCUCCAGAGAGCAGACCUGCGCGGCGGGAACUCCAGCAAGCCCUGGUGCCUGUGAUGAAAAAGCUGGUCCCAGUCAGGAGGAGGGCCUGGGGCCAGCUCUGCCUGCCCCCACAGCGGCUCAGAGUCACUCGACAUCCACUGAUCCCAGCUCCUGUCCUGGGCCUGCUGCUGCUGCUGCUGCUCUCUGUCCUGCUGCUUGGCCCGUCCCCACCUCCCACCUGGCCCCACCUCCAGCUCUGCUACCUCCAGCCCCCUCCAGUGUGAGAGGCUCUACUUGCCCCUCAGAGCAGUGUCUAGCUCAAUAAAUCCCCUGGCCCUCUCUCCACUGGGAUCCCCAUUGUUAGUCCACUGUUGCGCAGGCUUACCCUAGAUAGAGUACAGGGGAUCCACAUCCCUGUAUUUUUAUGUGAAGUCUCCUAGUUUUUUAAUGCUGACAUUUCUUAACAAUAGCAAAACUCCCCCAGUAAUGGAUUAAGCACUAAGGAUUAUUCCCUCACAAAACAAGCCUGGCGAGGGCAGCUGUGGGCACACAGCUAAGUCUCGGUUGCCUUGGGGUCAGGGCCUCAGUGAUUCUCCUGUCCCCUCCCUCAUGCUCAGGAGUUGGCAGUUGUAGCUUCCUACAUCACAUCUGCGGGAAACGGAAAUUUCUUCCUUCCUUUUUAUAAAGAGAGGCAGUAGCCUCAGUGUGCAGUGGGUAGAUUCAAAUCAUAUUCAUAAUAAAAGAGAAGCAGUUGCCUGCCCAGA